AGCCCCGCCUGCUUCCCGGCUCCAGCUGGGGCCGGAGAGGCUGAGUGGUUGGUACGCUGCUCGCUGGCCUCCCAGUCUUCCCAGCAACCGGUGACACUGCCCGCGCCAGACUGACCACUAGCCGACGCGGGCGAGAGGGACAGGAGCGUGACCUCCCCAUCCCGAGGGGCCGGACGCUCGGGCGCCUCCCCGCUCCCCCCACUCGGAGGCCGCGCGCGCCGUUAGCCCCUUCCUCGCUCCCCCGCCCCAGUCCCGCAGUCCGGGAGGCGGGGGUCGGCAGCCGGCUGAGUGGGAACCGCGCGGUGUCUGAGGAGGCAGUCGGCGACCGGUUUCCACUUCAAGCGUGACCCUUUUGCCUGUGGGAUGAGCUCCAGCAUGGGGUGAGGUACAGAAGAGAGACUUGAAGAGCGUGCCUUGGGACUCAAGCGCCAAACCUGUACCCUAGCGAGUGUCCUACUCCGCAUCCGUAAUGGAAGGAAAUGCACAUCUUACUCCAGAGGCACAAGAGGAGGACAUCCCAUGCGGCUACUCCUGCCCAGCGUGGUGGGGCAGCAGAAGCUCCAGAGCCCAGACUUGCAGAUUCAUCAUAUUCAAACCUUCACAAACAACUUGGAUAUCCUGACAAUUAUUAUAGAAUGGAUGCCCCUUGAUUCUCCCCAGCCUUUCCUGAAAAUGGGAAAAGUGUUCUUGGAUAAUGCCACCAACUUUUAAUAAUGUUUUUUGUGAAUUAUCUAUGCUCCCGUUUUUACCCCUUUACUGGGUCCUGAGUUGCUUUCUCAACUUUGGGGCUGUAUACUGGCAUGGGGUAGUGUGUUUAUCAAGUGCUGUCCAAAGCCAAGGAACAAUAUUUUGGGGUUUCUCAAAUACCUUCCCUUGGCCAGGCCCCAGCCCCUUCAGUAACUUCAGGGUCUGAGCCCUUUGCCUAGGCUGUUGCUGCUGGACCUGUUUGUGCUUCAUCACAUUACCCGCUUUGUUCUUCCAGCCCAAGUCUGGCUGGGUUCAUGUCAGUGACUCAGGAAAGCUGGGUUUUGGAGGAAGGCGUUGGUAUAGUCUAAACGCAGGGGACUUCUCACUGCCCCAUCCUGCCUUGGUCAUUUCCUAAUGCAUCCCCAGACAAGGAUCCCCAUCUAAGGCCAGCGAACAGGCUUGGCGUUCCUUUCCCUCAGAGCAGUGUUGAUGGUUCCCAGGCUAAAUGCAAGCUCCCCUUUGAAUCCAUUCCUGUUUGUUCUCCAGGACACUUGUAGUUUCCCUCCUGCCCUUCCAAGUGGUUCAAGGACACCCCCUCCCUAUUUCCGGGAUGCCCAUGGCUUUGCUUUGUCUUGGGGAAGGGAAUCCUGGAGAUGGACUACCUAAAGAAGUUAUAACAAAUAGGGAGUUCGUGUUCCCCUCUCCAUUCCUUAGGAGCUGCUGCAGAGGCUCACAAUGACCUUCUCCCCACAGGCUCACGGUGCAGGGUGAACCUGGCCACAGCUCACCCUGGAACAGCCACAAUGUCUGCCCCUUAGAGAAGAACCCUGAAAUCAGACCAGUUUUUGCGGCCUCCCCCUUUCCUCUCUGUUACAGUGCCCUUUCCAGGCCUUAAGAGAAGUAAAACUUAGCUGCAGCGUCAGGAGGUGGACCCCAGAGUGUGAGUGGCACGCUUCCCUGUGAACCCGUCCUCACCAUGUUUGCCACAUCUGGGGCAGUGGCAGCGGGGAAGCCUUACUCGUGCAGCGAAUGUGGCAAGAGCUUCUGCUACAGCUCAGUGCUGCUGCGACAUGAACGAGCUCACGGCGGUGACGGCCGCUUCCGUUGCCUAGAAUGCGGUGAGCGCUGUGCACGGGCUGCUGACCUCCGAGCGCACAGGCGCACGCAUGCUGGCCAGACCCUCUACAUCUGCAGUGAGUGCGGACAAAGCUUCCGCCACAGCGGCCGUCUUGACCUACACUUGGGCGCACACCGGCAGCGAUGCCGCACUUGCCCCUGCCGCACAUGCGGCCGGCGCUUCCCGCACCUCCCGGCGCUGCUGCUACACCGGCGCCGCCAGCAUCUGCCAGAGCGGCCCCGCCGCUGCCCGCUGUGCGCCCGCACCUUCCGGCAGAGCGCGCUGCUCUUCCACCAGGCGCGGGCGCACCCCUUGGGGACAACCUCUGACCCUGCUGCCCCACCCCACCGCUGCGCGCAGUGCCCGCGAGCCUUCCGAAGCGGCGCCGGGCUGCGGAGUCACGCGCGCAUCCACGUGUCCCGGAGCCCCACGCGACCCCGUGUCUCAGACGCCCACCAGUGUGGCGUGUGCGGCAAGUGCUUUGGCAAGAGCUCUACGCUGACGCGACACCUGCAGACGCACUCGGGGGAGAAACCCUUCAAGUGCCCGGAGUGCGGCAAGGGCUUCCUGGAGAGCGCCACGCUGGUGCGCCACCAGCGCACACACACGGGCGAGAAGCCGUACGCAUGUGGCGACUGUGGACGCUGCUUCAGCGAGAGUUCCACGCUGCUGCGCCAUCGGCGCAGCCAUCAGGGCGAGCGGCCACAUGCGUGCGCCACUUGCGGCAAGGGUUUCGGGCAGCGCUCCGACCUGGUGGUGCACCAGCGCAUCCACACGGGCGAGAAGCCCUUCGCGUGCCCCGAGUGCGGCCGCCGCUUCAGCGACCGCUCGGACCUCACCAAGCACCGGCGCACGCACACGGGCGAGAAGCCCUACCGCUGCGAACUGUGCGGCAAGCGGUUCACGUGCGUGUCCAAUCUCAACGUGCAUCGGCGCAACCAUGCCGGCCACAAGCCACACAAAUGCCCCGAGUGCAGCAAGGCCUUCAGCGUCGCCUCCAAGCUUGCACUGCACCGCAAGACGCACCUGGGCGAACGGCCAGCGGAGUGCGCAGAGUGCGGCAAGUGCUUCAGCCACAGCCGCUCGCUGUCACAGCAUCAGCGGGCCCACACGCGCGCCCGCACCGCUGCCGCCGUUGCCAUCCAGUCCGCAGUGGGCACUGCCCUCGUCUUUGAGGGGCCGGCUGAACAGGAAAAGCCAGGGUUCUCUGUGUCCUAGUUGAGGGAGGCUUGCUGAGGCUUCUCUAAAGGUGGUUGGGCAAGCACCUAUAUAGUAUCACGGGGACAGUUGAGGCAACUCGUAGAUGGAGAUUUGGGAAAAGACGAUGUGGCCUCCUACCUUUCCAGUUUCUGUUGGCAGCCCUUCACGUAGCCUCCUGCCUCGCCUCUACACCUACUACCCUGUCGGCCCUUUUGCCAUGCUGUCCUCGUAUAACUCGGAUUCUCUCCUCAGGUGUAGGUGCAGGGAGUCAGGGAACCCUUAGACUCCCCUGUGUGCAAGAGCCCAGGUGUUGGUGUGUCCCUUUAAUGCUACUGUGCUCUCUGGUGUUUCUGAUUUUCCUGCCUUUAUUCUGUCUUCUCUUGUCCUAUCUCAUUCCAGCCCACAUCUUCUCCUUUCCUGAUUACUUUUGUUGUCCUGCCUCUUCAGGUAAUGGUCACAGAUUUGGCUGUAGGCACGUUACCAGCCCUGUGGCUUCUUGACUCUUGGUUCCCUGUUAACUCUGUUUCUGAGAAAUGUGGGUAUGGAGGUGGGUGGGAAAGCUCACUUCCAUGAAGGAUGUCUCCAUGCUAGGAGCUGCCUGCACCCUGGCAGAGGUGGCCAGUCACGUGAAGGUGGGCAGGGCCCUUAGCAUGGCCACACAUGUCCCCAGGGCAGAUCAAGGGGCCUCUCAGAACCAUGUUCCCCAGCCAGGUGAGGACCAUUUUCACUGGGACCCAGGCCAAAACCAUGUGGGUGCACAAAGCCAGGCACUGCCAAGUGGAACAUGAGGUUAUUUCCAAAUCAUGGGAGCCACCAGCAGGGAGAGGGCAGGAUGGAAAAUCCCCUGGAGCCGGUCAACUUUUUGCUCAUGGCUAGUGAAAUAAAGUUGUUUGAGUACUAGA